AGAGGUCCCGGGCGCACCUGCAGAGCCGGAGGCUUGCUGGGGCAUGCGCUCCAUGAAGGCUCUGCAGAAGGCCCUGAGCCGGGCUGGCAGUCACUGCGGGCGAGGAGGCUGGGGUCACCCGAGCCGGAGCCCCCUCCUUGGCGGGGGCGUCCGGCACCACCUCAGUGAGGCCGCGGCGCAGGGCAGAGAGACGCCACACAGCCACCAGCCGCAGCACCAGGAUCAUGAUUCAUCAGAAAGUGGCAUGCUGUCCCGCCUGGGUGAUUUGCUCUUUUACACUAUUGCUGAAGGACAGGAACGAAUCCCUAUCCACAAGUUCACCACUGCACUAAAGGCCACUGGACUGCAGACAUCAGAUCCUCGGCUCCGAGACUGCAUGAGCGAGAUGCACCGCGUGGUCCAAGAGUCCAGUAGUGGUGGCCUCUUGGACCGAGAUCUCUUCCGAAAGUGUGUGAGCAGCAACAUUGUGCUCCUGACCCAGGCAUUCCGAAAGAAGUUUGUCAUUCCUGAUUUUGAGGAGUUCACGGGCCAUGUGGAUCGCAUCUUUGAGGAUGUCAAAGAGCUCACUGGAGGCAAAGUGGCAGCCUACAUCCCUCAGCUGGCCAAGUCAAACCCAGACCUGUGGGGUGUCUCCCUGUGCACUGUGGAUGGUCAACGGCACUCUGUGGGCCACACAAAGAUCCCCUUCUGCCUGCAGUCCUGUGUGAAGCCCCUCACCUAUGCCAUCUCCAUAAGCACCCUAGGCACUGACUACGUGCACAAGUUUGUGGGCAAAGAGCCAAGUGGCCUGCGCUACAACAAGCUCUCCCUCAAUGAGGAAGGAAUCCCCCAUAACCCCAUGGUCAAUGCUGGUGCCAUUGUUGUCAGCUCCCUGAUCAAGAUGGACUGUAACAAAGCAGAGAAGUUUGAUUUUGUGUUGCAGUAUCUCAACAAAAUGGCUGGGAAUGAAUACAUGGGUUUCAGCAAUGCCACGGAAGGUAAUUUUUCCCCUUCUCCCAACACCCACUCCUCCAACUUCAAGUACUAAAUUGGGUGUUUGCUUCAGAUUCCAGUCAGAGAAGGAAACAGGGGAUCGGAAUUAUGCCAUCGGCUAUUAUCUCAAGGAAAAGAAGUGCUUUCCUAAGGGGGUGGACAUGAUGGCUGCCCUUGAUCUCUACUUCCAGCUGUGUUCUGUGGAGGUCACUUGUGAAUCAGGCAGUGUCAUGGCAGCCACCCUCGCCAACGGUGGGAUCUGCCCCAUCACAGGCGAGAGUGUGCUGAGUGCUGAAGCAGUGCGCAACACCCUCAGCCUCAUGCAUUCCUGCGGCAUGUAUGACUUCUCUGGCCAGUUUGCCUUCCACGUGGGCCUGCCAGCCAAGUCAGCUGUAUCAGGAGCCAUCCUCCUGGUGGUACCCAAUGUCAUGGGAAUGAUGUGCCUGUCACCCCCAUUGGACAAGCUGGGGAACAGCCAUAGGGGGACCAGCUUCUGCCAGAAGUUGGUGUCUCUCUUCAAUUUCCACAACUAUGACAACCUGAGGCACUGUGCUCGGAAGUUAGACCCACGGCGUGAAGGGGCAGAAAUUCGGAACAAGACUGUGGUCAACCUGUUAUUUGCUGCCUAUAGUGGCGAUGUCUCAGCUCUUCGAAGGUUUGCCUUGUCAGCCAUGGAUAUGGAACAGAAAGACUAUGACUCGCGCACAGCUCUGCAUGUUGCUGCAGCUGAAGGACACAUCGAAGUUGUUAAAUUCCUGAUCGAGGCUUGCAAAGUGAAUCCUUUUGCCAAGGACAGGUGGGGCAACAUUCCCCUGGAUGAUGCUGUGCAGUUCAACCAUCUGGAGGUGGUCAAACUGCUUCAAGAUUACCAGGACUCCUACACACUCUCUGAAACUCAGGCUGAGGCAGCAGCUGAGGCCCUGUCCAAAGAGAACUUAGAAAGCAUGGUAUGAGCACAGGUCAUGGACAGCCCCUGCUCAAGAAAAAGCAUGAGCUGGCCACACAUGUAAUCCAUAACCACCAAAAAUACUAUGGAGAGCUACACUGCUUCAGUGGGGACCAAGCAGUCAUUUGGUGACUUAGGCUAGUGCUUUCUAUGGGAGUCAAAAUACCCCAUUCCCUCAGCAGACAGAGUACAGAGAAGGGCCUCAGAGGACACCUGCAGUACAGCUAUCCAGAGAGACUGGGCUUCAAGGUACAGCCUAAUGGCUUGCCCCACUCAAAACCAUCCCAGCUCUUCACCCAGGUCUCCUCUUCCUCUCCCUGAAGAAACCAUCAUGAGAGAGAUACUCUGGUGGAGGGACUCUAGCUACCAUGCACAUGUACAUAUCCACAGAAUAUGGGAAGUGGGAAUGGCUAUAUACAUGGCUUUAGUAGUCUGGAGAAAUCUACUCCCCUUGGCCAGGACAUGCUGCUGCUACUGCUAACAGCCAAUUUUAUAGACAGAGAAAGUAUUUUGUGUUCAAAUAAACUUUAAUUACCAAAUCA